GGAUUCCCUCUUUCUCUAUCUUUUGGAAUAGAGUCAGGAUUGGUACCAAUUUUUCUUUGAAUGCCUGGUACGAUUCAGCUGUGAGUCUGUCUGGUACUGGGCCUUUUUGUUUUUUUUUUUUUGGUGUUUUGUUGUUGUUGUUGUUGUUGUUUUGUUUUGUUUUGUUUUUUUGAGACAGAGUCUGGCUGUGUCACCCAGGCUGAAGUGUAGUGGCACAGUCUUGGCUCAAGCAGUUCUCCUGUCUCAGCCUCCAGAGUAGCUGGGAUUACAGGCGUGUGCCACCAUUCCUGGCUGAUUUUGUAUUUUUAGUAGAGAUGUGGUUUCACCAUGUUGGCCAGGCUGGUUUGAACUCCUGACCUCUGGUGAUCCACCCACCUUGGUCUCUCAAAGUGCUGGGAUUACAGGUGUGAGCCACUGCGCCUGGCCUAUGUUGGCAAUUUUUUAAUUGCCAUGUCAAUCUCACUGUAUGUUAUUGGUCUUUCAGGGUAUCUACUUCUUCCUGAUUUAAGCUAGGAGGGUUAUAUCUUUCUGGGAAUUUAUCCAUCUCCUCUAGGUUUUCUAGUUUAUAUGCAUAAAGGUGUUGAAUUAGCCUUGAAUGAUCUUUUAUAUUUCUGUGGUGUCAGUUGUAUUAUCUCCCAUUUUGUUUCUAGUUGAGCUUAUUUGUUUUUUUUUUUUUCCUCAGCUUUUCUUGGUUAAUCUUGCUAAUGGUCUAUUAAUUUUAUUAACCUUUUCAAAGACCCAGCUUUUUGUUUCAUUUAUCUUUUUUUGUUUUUUUUUUUUUUUUUUUUUUUUUUUUUACACUUUUAAGUUCUAGGGUACAUGUGCACAAGGUACAGGUUUGUUACAUAGGUAUACAUGUGACAUGUUGGUUUGCUGCACCCAUUAACUCAUCUCAUUUAUCUUUUGUAUUUUUUUUUUUGUUUCAAUUUCAUUUAGCUCUGCUCUGAUCUUAGUUAUAUUCUUUCUUGUGCUGUGUUUGGGUUUGGUUUGUUCUUGUUUCUGUAUUUCCUUGAGGUGUGACCUUAGAUUGUCUGUUUGUGCUCUUUCAGACUUUUUGAUUUAGGCAUUUAGGGCUAUGAACUUUCCUCCUAGCCCCGCCUUUGCUAUAUCCCAGAAGUUUUAUAGGUUGUAUCUCUAUUGUCAUUCAGUUUGAAGAACUUUUUAAUUUCCAUCUUGAUUUCAUUGUUGACCCAGUGAUCAUUCAGGAGCAGGUUAUUUAAUUUCUAUGUGUUUGCAUGGUUUUGAAGUUUCCUUUUGGAGUUGAUUUCCAGUUUUUUUCCACUAUGGUCUGAGAGAGUGCUUGAUAUAAUUUCAAUUUUAUUAAAUUUAUUGAGGCUUGUUUUGUAGCCUAUGAUAUGAUCUACCUUGGAGAAAGUUCCAUGUGUAAUGAAUAGAAUGUAUAUUCUGCAGUUGUUGGGUAGAAUGUUCUGUAAAUAUCUGUUGAGUCCAUUUGUUUCAGGGUAUAGUUUAAAUCCAUUAUUUCUUUGUUGACUUUCUGUCUUAAUGACCUGCCUAGUGCUGUCAGUGGAGUUGAAGUCCCCCACUAUUAUUGUGUUGCUGUCUAUCUCAUUUCUUAAGUUUUAUCAGUUUGGGAACUCCAGUGUUAGGUACUUAUAUAUUUAGGAUUGUGAUAUUUUUCUGUUGGAUAAUGCUUUUUAUCAUUAUAUAAUGUCCCUCUUUGUCUUUUUUAAGUGCUGUUGCUUUAAAGUUUGUUUUAUCUGAUAUAAGAAUAGCUACUCCUGCUUGCUUUUGAUAUUCAUUUGCAUAGAAUGUCUUUUUCCACCCCUUUACCUUAAGCUUAUGUGAGCCCUUAUGUGUUAGGUGAGUCUCUUCAAGGCAGGAGAUAGUUGGUUUGUGAAUUCGUAUCCAUUCUGCAAAUUCAUGUCUUUUAAGUGGAGCAUUUAGGCCAUUUACAUUUAAUGUUAAUGAUAUGGUUUGGCUGUGUCCGUACUCAAAUCUCAACUUGCAUUGUAUCUCCCAGAAUUUCUAUGUGUUGUGGGAGGGACCCAGGGGGAGGUAAUUGAAACAUGGGGACCAGUCUUUCUCAUGCUAUUCUCGUGAUAGUGAAUAAGUCUCAUGAGAUUUGAUGGGUUUAUCAGGGGUUUCCGCUUUUGCUGCUUCCUCAUUUUUCUCUUGCCACUGCCAUGUCAGAAGUGCAUUUUGCCUCCCGCCAUGGUUCUGAGACAUCCCCAGCCAUGUGGAACUGUAAGUCCAAUUAAACCUCUUUUUCUUCCCAAUCUCAGGUAUGUCUUUAUCACCAGCAUGAAAAUGGACUAAUACAGUUAGUGUUUAGUUGUGAGGUACUAUUCUGUUCAUCAUGCUGUUUGUUGCCUUUAUACCUUGGUUUUUUGUUUGUUUGUUUAUUGUAUUUUUGCUUUAUAGGUCCUAUGAGAUUUAUGCUUUAAAGAGGUUCUGUUUUGAUGUGUUUCCGAGAUUUGUUUCAAGAUUUAGAGCUCCUUAUAGCAGUUUUUACAGUGUUAGCUUGGUAGUGAUGAAUUCACUCAUCAUUUGUUUGUCUGAAAAAGACUGUAUGUUUCCUUAAUUUAUGAAGCUUAGUUUCACUGGAUACAAAACUCUUAGCUGAUAAUUGUUUUGUUAAGCAGGCUGAAGAUAGGGCCCCAAAUCCUUCAAGCUAGGAGGGUUUGCCGAGAAAUCUGCUGUUUAUGUGAUAGGUUUUCCUUUAUAGAUUACCUGAUGCUUUUGCCUUACAGCUCAUAAGAUAGGUUUUCCUUUAUAGAUUACCUGGUGCUUUUGCCUUGUAGCUGAUAAGAUUCUUUCCUUCAUCUUAACUUUAGAUAAUCUGAUGCCAGUGUGCCUAGGUGAUGCUCUUUUUGCAGUGAAUUUCCCAGGUGUUCUUUGAGCUUACUGUAUUUGGAUAUCUAGGUUUUUAACAAGGCCCGGGAAGUUUUCCUUGACUAUUCUCCCAAAUACGUUUUCUAAACUUUUCGCUUUCUCUUCUUCCUCAGGAAUGCUGAUUAUUCUUAGGUUUGGUUGUUUAACAUAAUCUCAGACUUCUUGGAGGCUUUGUUCAUAUUUUCUUAUUCUUUUUUCUUUGUCUUUGUUGGAUUAAUUAAAAAGCCUUGUCAAGCUCUAAAGUUCUCUUCUGCUUGGUCAGUUUUGUUGCUGAGACUUUCUAGAGCAUUUUGCAUUUCUAUAAAUGUGUCCAUUAUUUCCUGAAGUUUUGAUUGUUUUUUAUUUAUGCUAUCUAUUUCACUGAAGAUUUCUCCCCUUAUUUCUUGUAUGAUUUUUUUGAUUUCCUUAAAUUAGGCUUCACCUUUCUCUGGUGCCUCCUUGAUUAGCUUAAUAACUGACCGUCUGAAUUCUUUUUCAGGUAAAUCAGGGAUUUCUUCUUGGUUUGGAUCCACUGCUGGAAUGUGGCUUUCUGAGAGCUGAGCUGUAGUGAUUGUUAUCUCUCUUUAAAAUUAAAUACCUAGUAACUAACCGAAGAUGUGAAAGAUACCUACAAUGAAGACUGUAAAACACUGAUGAAAGAAAUUGAAGAGGACACAAAAAAAUUAAAAGAUACUUCAUGUUUGUGGAUUAGAAAAAUCGAUAUUGUUAAAAUGUUCAUACUGCUUAAAGCAGUCUGCAGAUUCAGUGCAGUCCCUAUCAAAGCAUCGAUGACAUUCUUCACAGAAAUAGAGAAAACAAUCCUAAAAUUAAUAUGGAACCACAGAAGACUGAGAAUAGCCAACACUAUUCUGAACAAAAGGAAGAAAACUGAAGGAAUCACAUUACCUUACUUGAAGUUAUACUGCAGAGCUAUAGUAACUAAAACAGCAUGGUACUAGCAUAAAAACAGACCAAACAGUAGAACAGAAUAGAUAUCCCGGAAACAAAUCCAUAUACCUACAGCGGGUGAACUCAUGUUUGACAAAGAUGUCAAGAACAAACAUUUGCGAGAAGACAGUCUCUUCAAUAAAUGGUGCUGGGAAAACUGGCUAUUCACAUACAGAAGAAUGAAAUUAGAUCUGUUAUCUCUCACUAUAUAUAAAAAGGCAAAAUGGAUUGCUUAAAUCUAAGACCCCAAACUAUGAAACUGCUAGAAGAAAUCAUUGGGGAAACUCUCUAGGACAUUGUUCUGGGCAAAAGAAUUUUCAUAAGCCUUGGUAAUCAAAUGAAAAAUGGACAAAUUGGAUCACUUCAAGUUAAGCUUCUGCACAGCAAAGGAAACAAUCUACAAAGUAAAGAGACAAGGCACAGAAUGGGAGAAAAUAUUUGUAAACUACAUGUUUGACAUGGCAUUAAUAACCAGAAUAUAAGAAGCUCAUACGACUCUGUAGGAAAGAAUCUAAUAAUCCAAUUAUACAAUGGUAAUACCUGAAUAGACAUUUCUCAAAAGGAGAGAUACAAAUGGAAAACAGGCAUGUGAAUAGCUACCUAAUGUCAUUGAUCAUCAACAAAAUGCAAAUCAAAGCUACAGUGAGAUAUCACACCUCAUUUAAAAUAGCUCUUAUUCAAAAGACAGGUAAUAUGAAAUGCAGGUGAGGAUGUGUAGAAAGGGAAUCCUUGUACAUUGUUGGUGGGGAUGUAAAUUUGUACAACCAGUAUGGAGACCAGUUUGGAGGUUCCUUAAAAAACUAAAAAUAGAGCUACCAUGCAAUCCAGCGAUCCAGGUGCUGAAUAUAUACCCAAAUGAAAGGAAAUCAGUAUAUCAAAGGGAUAUCUGCAAUUCCAUGUUUGUUGCAGCACUGUUCACAAUAGCCAAGAUUUGGAAGCAACCUAAGUGCUCAUCAGCAGAUAAAUGGAUAAAGAAAAUGUGGUACAUAUACACAAUAGAAUACUAUUCAGCCAUGCAAAAGAAUGAGAUCUGUCAUUUGCAACAAUGUGGAUGGCUCUAGAGGUCAUUAUCUUCAGUGAAAUAAGCCAGGCACAGAAAGGCACACUUAUGUUCUCACUUAUUUGUGGGAGCUAAAAAUUAAAACAUUUGAAUUUGUGGUGAGAAUAGAAGGAUGGUUACCAUAGGCUGGGAAAGGUAUUUUGUGUUGGGGAAGAAGGUGGGGGUGGUUAAUGGGUAUAAAAAGUAGUUAGAAUGGGCCAGGCACAGUGGCUUACACCUGUAAUCCUAGCACUUUGGGAGGCCGAGGCAGGUGGAUCACCUGAGGCCAGGAGUUCAAGACCAGCCUGGCCAACAUGGCGAAACUGCCUCUCUACUAAAAAACACAAAAGUUAGCCUGGUGUGGUAGUGAUGGGCACCUGUAAUCCCUGCUACUCAGGAGGCAGAGGCAGCAGAAUCACAUGAACCCAGUAGGCGGAGGUUGCAUUGAGCCAAGAUCACACCACUGCACUCCAGCCUGGGCAACAGAGCAAGACUCUGUCUCAAAAAAAAGUAGUUAGAAUGAAUUAAGACCUAGUUAACCUAGUAUUUAAUUGCACAACUGGGUGACUAUAGUCAUCAAUAAUUUAGUUAUACAUUUAAAAAUAACUAAGACUAUAAUUGGAUUGUUUGUAACACAAAGGAUAAAUGCUUCAGGGGAUAGAUACCCCAUUUACCAAUGUGAUUAUUAUGCAUUGCAUUUCUGUAUCAAAUUAUCUUAUGUACGCACAGAAGUUACAAAUUAAAACUGGAAAUGAAACCUCAUGAAAGUAUAAGAAUCAGAGGUCAUAUAAAACAAUCACAUAAAGGAAGAGAAAGGAAUCAAAUGGCAACACAGUGUAAUUCCAUUAUACCACAAAGACGAGGAAAACAAGGAAAGAAUUUAUACAACAACUAGGUAAUAAUCGAUAAUGUGACAGGAUCAAAACCUCUCAUAUUAAUAUUAACAUGGAACCUGAAUGGAUGAAAUGCUCCACUGAAAAGAGAGGUUGAUGGAAUGGAUUUUCAAAACCCAUCAACCACGUAUAUGCUGCUUACCAGAAAUGUGUCUUACAUGGUAAGACACAUUUAGACUCAAGUUGAAGGGGUAGAAAAAGAUAUUCUGUGCAAUGGAAACCAAAAUUGAGCAGGAGCAGCUAGACAUAUCUCACAUACAAUUAGCUUUAAAUCAAAAGCAGUAAAGAAAGACAAACAUGAUCAUUAUUUAAUGAUAAAGGGAUCAAUUCAACAAGAGGAUAUAACAAUCCUAAAUAUGCAUGCACUGAACACUGGGCCACCCAGAUUCAUUAAAUAUUACUAUAGUUAAAGAAAGAGAUAGAUAGCUGAACAAUAAUGGUAGGGAACAACACCACACUCAUACUAGACAGAAAUUGAUAAUCUGGUCCUAAAAUUUAUAUGGAAAUUCAAGGGACCCACAAUAGCCAAAACAGUCUUCUCCAAGAAUAACAAAGUUGGAGGACUUAACACAUCCUGAAUUCCAAACUUCUCACAAAUGACAGUAAUCAAGAUAAUGUGGUACAGACCUAUACACAAAUGGAAUAGAAUCGUGAACCCAGAAAUACACCUUCUCAUUUAAAGUCAAUUUGUUUUUUAUGAGGGUGUCAUAAAAAAGGUAAGUAAUGGUGUUUUAAAAUUGUGCUGGAACAAUUGGAUGUCCACGUCGGUCGUGGAGACCCUAACCCAGUGGCACUAGAGGAAUUAAAGACACACACACAGAAAUAUAGAGUGCGGAGUGGGAAUCAGGGGGCUGACAGCCUUCAAAGCUGAAAGCCACAAACAGAGUUUUACCCACAUAUUCAUUGACAGCAAGCCAGUGGUAAGCAUUGUUUCUAUAGAGUAUAGAUUAACUAAAAUGGGAAACAAAGGGAUGGGCUCUGGCUAGUUAUCUGCAGCAGGUAUAUGUCCUUAAGGCACAGACACUCAUGCUAUUGUUUGUGGUUCAGGAACGCCUUAAGCGGUUUUCCACCCCAGGUGGGCCAGGUGUUCCUUGCCCUCAUUCUGGUAAACCAACAACCUUCAGCGUGGGCAUCAUAGCUAUCACAAGCAUGUCACACUGCUGCAGAGAUUUUGUUUAUGGCCAGUUUUGGGGCCUGUUGAUGGCCAGAUUUGGGGGCCUGUUCCCAACAUGUCCCCCUUUUUUGUUUUUGCAAGACGAUAGAAGCAAAGGCGGCUUUAUCACGGUGAGCUACUUCUUGCAGGAGUCAGGAUCCACAUCUGCAGACUAUACAAAGACAACACAGAUUAAAAGUGCAAUCAUCAUUGAAAUCACAGAGCCUCCAAGUGUUUUUAUCCAUUUUAAUGGGUUAAUAGCUGCUAAUCUGUCUGCAGCUCCUUCAAGCACUCCAGUUCCUGGCAUUAAGGUCAGGUGUGCCUGGGAUGCUUUAAAUAUUUGUUCUUUUAAUUUUGCAAUGUCCAACGACAAGUUUGUAGAGUGCCCUUCUAGAUGCUUUUUUAUUCUGUCCCAAAUUUUGAUCUUAUUAAGAGCCGUUAAUAGUUUCCACAAAUCCUUAUGUUUAGCUCCUAGAGCGGGCCAUAUCAUUUGAGGUUGAGGUGCCACUAUACUGCCGUGUUUCCAGAUAAUAGGAACUCUUGCCAUACUUCUUACCAUUUCUACCAUCUGACCGUUUUGUUCAGACCAACUGAACAUAGUGUGGCCAUGGCACGCAGACUGAGAGGUACAAUUUGUGCUAAACAUCCCCUUAGGGGACCAAUCAAUAAUGAUUCCAUGGGAAUCGUUGCGCAGCACCUCUGCCUGUUCUGCAGUGCAAUCUUCCCAAACAAGUACGUUCAUUUUUUCGGGCCAGGUCCAAUUCUGUUUACAAACAGGUUUUUGAUGGCAGUAUGCCUCAAUUAUAGGAGCAGAUUUAUUAUGGUAAAUAGUGAGACCAGAAAGCAUGUGUAACUGUGUCAUAGAAUGAUUACAUCCAGGCAUUAUUGCCAGCCAAGAUUGAUAGUGAGGGGGUAGGCAACUGGUGACCUUUCCCAAACAGAUAGGUGAAUGUUCAAAUCCUAAAGAAAUAUUCCUAACAGUUCCUUCCUCAUGUGGGUGAGACGGGCCUCUAUUAUCUGUAGGACCGAGCAUCCAAGAGCUAUCAUUAGUGUAUACCUCCACUGGGGGGUCCAGCCAAGUUACAGGCCAUAGAAGUGGUGGAAAAGGUAAAUAUACCCAAUAAGUAUAAUUGUUCUCUGUGUCAGCCCUUGCUAAAGGAAUACUCAUGGCAAUGGUGAUCACUGCUAUCAUAGCUAUCAUUAAAUUACUCAUUGUGAUUGGUUGUUCCGCUUUCCUCAGGUUUUCUUCCGCCGUCUGUGACAGCUUCUUGAUCUGUCCCCAGGUAGGUGGCUGCAUUCGACAGGUGUUGCUCGUGACAGUUGGGGUCCUCCUCAGUGUCAGUCUCAACAUGGCUGCAACUGGUGUGUGUUUGGAAUCCUCCCAAAACCUCUUCCGGAGUAUCUGGCUCAUAGUAAGGCUUUAGGUAUCUCAGUGGCACCCAAAUUGGCUGUUGAUUCAGUCCUGGCAAAACACAAGCAUAACCUCUACCCCAAAUUAUUAUUUUACCUGUUUCCCAAUUUUUGUUAUUGCAUCUCUCCACCAAACCAGUUGUUCUGCUUCUGCCUUUGCAGCUGGUUUCUGUAGAUGCUGUUCAGCUGCUGAUAGCAUCUGGCCUUUAGGCAGGCUCAAAAAAUGUAAAGUCAGUAAUGCUAGAUUCAGUUGCAUAUUCAUGAUGUCCUGUAGUCUCUGUUUCCCUCCUUUUGCUUUUGCAACGGCUGUUUCGGGGAGAGAUUCAUUCAUUCCACAAUGGGUUGUCCUUGAGAAUUACAUGGGAUGCCAGUAAUGUGUUUAAUAUUCCAUACAGAGAAAAAUGUAGCUAGAGCUUGGUUAGUAUAUAUAGCCUGGGGCAUUGUCCAUUUUAAUAGAUGCUGGAAUGCCCAUCACCGCAAAAUACUGCAAAAGAUGAUGUUUAACACAGGCAGAAGACUGUCCUGAUUGGCAUGUAGCCCAGACAAAAUGAGAAAAGGUAUCUACACAUACAUGAACAUAAGCUAGUCUCCCAAACGAGGGAACAUGGGUGACAUCCAUUUGCCAAAGAGAAUUAGGUUCUAAUCUGCGAGGAUUAACUCCUCCUAUAAAAGAUGAGGAAUGCACCAUUUGGCAAGUUGGGCAUCGCUGGAUAAUAGCUUUAGCUUCUUUCCAGGUAAUGCUAUACCUGCGUUUGAGACCAGAGGCAUUAACAUGGGUUAAAUUGUGAAAGUGUCUGUCUUAGAUACUGCAGUAGCAACUAGGUGAUCAGCCAUUUGAUUCCCUGCAGUCCAAGGUCCUGGAAGAGGUGUGUGAGUCCUAAUGUAAAUGAUGUAAAAGGGUGCAUUCUACUCCUAACUGCUGUUUGCAAUUGGGAAAAUAAUCAGUUGUUCAUCUGUGUGAAAUCGUAACUGAGCAUUUUCAAUUAAUUGUGUGGAAUGAACCACCUAUGAAGAAUCAGAAAUCACAUUAAUAGGCAUAUCGAAGGCAGUCAAUACCUCAAUUACAGCUACAAGCUCUGCUUUUUGAGCUGAAGUAUAGGGCAUCUGAAAUACUUUACCUUUCAAGCCAGAAUAAGAAGCUUUACCAUUACUAGACCCACCUGUGAAGACAUUUUCAGCACCUUCAGUUGGUUAAAAUUUAGUUAUUUUAGGGAGAAUCCAAUUAGUUAAUUUCAAAAAUUGAAACAGUUUUGUUUUAGGAAAAUGGUUAUUGAGAAUAUCCACAAAGUCAGCUAAAUGAGUUUGCCAAGUAAGACUAUUUAUAAAAGCUUGCUGUAUUUGUGCCUUUGUGAGAGGGACAAUUUUUCCAGGAUCAUAUCCAUGUAAUUUAACAAUCUGAGUUCUCUGAUUUCCUAUCACAGUAGCAAUUUGAUCUAAAUAAGGAGUUAGAGUCCGUGAAUUAGUAUGUGGAAGAAAAGCCACUGUACAAGAUCUUGCUCUUGAACAAUAACACCAGUAGGUGAAUCUGAGUUGAAAAAAAUUAGAAAUCUAGAGUCUUCUCUGGAUCUUUUCUACUUAUUUGAGCCUUAUGCACUUGCUUCUCAAUUAGCUGGAACUCUGCCUCCACCUCCUUUGUUAAUUGCUGAGGGCUAUUGCGACUAGGAUCUCCUCUAAGGAUAGAAAAUAGAUCACUCGUGGCAUAGGUAGGAAUGCCUACAGCAGGUUGUAUCCAAUUUAUGUCCCCUAGUAAUUUUUGAAAGUCACUUAAUGUUUUCAAUUGAUCCCUACGUAUGGUUGCUUUCUGUGGCACAAUGGUAGUAUCAUUUACUAAGGUCCCCAAGUAGGAGUAAGGAGUAGUAGUCUGAAUUUUGUCAGGAGCUAUGAUUAAACCAGCACAAGAAAUCAAAAUUUGCAAGUGAUCAUAAGAUUGGAGUAAUAAUUCUCUAGUGGGGCAGCACAAAGUAUAUCAUCCAUAUGAUGAAUAAUGUAACACUGUGGACAUUUUUUACGAGUAGAUUCAAUUGCUUGCCCUACAUACGUCUGGCAAAUUGUUGGACUGUUUAGCAUGCCUUGUGGCAACACUUUCCAGUGAAAAUGCUUAGCAGGCUGCAGGUUGUUUACCGCAGGAAUUGUAAAUACAAGCCAUUCACAGUCUUGCUCAGCUAAGGGGUUAGUAAAGAAACAGUCUUUUAAAUCUAUGACUAUUAAAGGCCAAUUUUUCAGAAUCAUAGCAGGAGAAGGCAGUCCUGGCUGCAAUGCCCCCAUAGGUUGUAUAACUGAAUUAAUGGCCCUUAAGUCAGUUAACAUUAUCCAUUUACCUGAUUUUGUCUUAAUUACGAAAACUGGAGAAUUCCAAGGGGAAAAUGUUGGAGCUAUGUGUCCUUUUUCUAAUUGUUCAGUAACUAAGUCCUCUAAAGCCUCCAGUUUCUCUUUGCUCAGCAGCCAUUGUUCUAUCCAAAUUGGCUUAUCUGUUAACCAUUUUAAAGGUAUAGGUUCUGGAGGCUUAACAAUGGCCACCAUCAAAAAUGAUAUCCUAAACCUUGGCGGGACUUUGUCUUUCCACUUGAAGCAGUUCCUUCAAACUUUGCAAAUUUUUUCCUAGCCCCAUACCAGGGACAUACCCCGUUUCAUGCAUCAUAUGUUGACUUUGAGGGCUGUAUAAUUGCUCUGGAAUUAGAACUUGUUCUCCUCAUUGUUGUAAUAAAUCUCUCCCCCAUAAAUUUAUAGGUAUAGAAGUUACAAUUGGUUGAAUAGUCCCAGGUUGUCCCAUCAGGCCCUUCACAAUGCAAGAUAUAACUAUUUUGAUAUACUUCAGGGGCUUUACGAACUUCAGCUAUGUUAAAUUGAGCAGGUUGAAUUGGCCAUGAGGACAGCCAGUGCUGUAGAGAAAUGAAUGAAAUGUCUGUUCCUGUAUCUACCAAACUUUUAAAUUUCUUUCCCUGAACAGUUAUUUCACAGAUAGGACAUUUAUCAGUAAUUUGAUUCCCCCAAUAAGCUGCUUUGCCUUGUUUAUUUGUGCUUCCAAAUCCUCCUGUUCGUUUAGUUUCACUUUUCCCCAUUUCCACAUAUGGCACAAUCAGGAGCUGCGCUAUACACGCUCCUGGCUCUGCUUUCCAGGGAACAGAAGUAGAUACUGCAAUUUGAAUUUCCCCAUUGUAAUCUGAAUUAAUGACUCCUGUAUGUACUUGCAUUCCUUUUAAAUUUAAACUAGAGGCCAGGUGCAGUGGCUCACGCCUGUAAUCCCAGCACUUUGGGAGGCCGAGGCAGGCAGAUCACGAGGUCAGGAGAUCAAGACCAUCCUGGCUAACAUGGUGGAACUUCGUCUCUACUAAAAAUACAAAAAAUUAGCCAGGCGUGGUGGCGGGCACCUGUAGUCCCAUCUACUCAGGAGGCUGAGGCAGGAGAAUGGCGUGAGCCUGGGAGGCGGAGCUGGCAGUGAGCCGAGACCACACCACUGCACUCCAGCCUGGGUGACAGAGUGAGACUCCAUCAAAUAAAUAAAUAAAUAAAUAAAUUUAUUUAAACUAGACCUACCUAGAAGUAAUGCUGGCAUCAUCUGGCUGGAGACAGCAACAUUCUUGAACAGUCCUGUUACAAAAGGAGAACCUGGUCUAUAAUGAUUUAUAGCUUGUUUACAUUCUUUAAGUAUUUUAAAAGGAAAAGGCUCAAACGUAGCUAUGAUAUUUCCCUGUUGAUAUGGGUGGUGUAUUCUGACAGGGAACUGCCAAGCCUCUAUAUCACCCUCUCGUCUAGCUUGCUGAAUUCCUGCCUGAAAAGAACUGAGAGCGGUCGCUCAAGGCACUGCCCAAACAGUUACUGGGGCAUCUACUUUUCACCCACUGUCCUCUGGAAAAAGAUCUGGAGGGUCAGGCCACUCUUUUUCUUCAAAAUAAUGAGGGGGUGCAGAAGGGUAGGGACAAACCUCUCCCUCCUUUGCCACUUUAGCUUUAGCUGGCCGACAAACCUGCUCUGUUACCUCUUAUGUUACUUCAUUACACCCUCCUUCCUCCUCCUCAUCAGUGUGAAAAGGUUCCAAGGUGGAACGAGCCAGAGCCCAUACUUGUCCCAUUGUUACCCUGAUGCUUCCGAGCUCCCCUUCUUACCACAGGGAUUGCUUAAGAGUACUCGGGUGUCCUCCAGCGUAGUUCCAUGUUCUCCAGUCAUUGUUCCGGCACACGCAUAGAAAUAUAGAGUGUGGAGCAGGAAUCGGGGCUGAUAGCCUUCAUAGCUGAGAGCCACGAAGAGUUUUACCCACAUAUUUAUUGAUAGCAAGCCAGUGAUAAGCAUUGUUUCUAUAGAUUAUAGUUUAAAUCGGGAAACAAAAGGAUGGGCUCUGGCUAGUUAUCUGCAGCAGGAACAUGUCUUUAAGGCACAGAUCACUCAUGCUAUUGUUUGCAGUUCUGGAAUGCCUUAAGGGGUUUUCUGCCCUGGGUGGGCGAGGUGUUCCCUUGCCCUAAUUCUGGUAAACCAACAACCUUCAGCGUGGGCAUCAUAGCCAUCACGAGCCUGUCACACUGCUGCAGAGAUUUUGUUUAUGGCCAGUUUUGGGGUCUGUUUAUGGCUAGAUUUGGGGUCCUGUUCCCAACAGACCCCUAUCUCUCACCAUAAGCAAAACUUAACUGAAAAUGGAUCAAAAACCUAAAUAUAAGCACUUAUAAAACUUUAAAAUUCUUAGGACCUUGGAUUAGGCUGUGAUAUACUUGCUAAAAACACACGUAAAUGUGUUUUUAAAUCUUUAGAAAUUAUGCUUUAUGAAAAUUUUACACUGUUUUCAAAGCAUACCAUCAAGGAAUGGGAAAGACAAUCCAUAUAAUGCGAGGGAAAGUUUGUAAAUUGUAUCUUAUAAGGGACUUAAUCUAAAAUAUAUAAGGAACUCUUACAAGCCAGUAAUAAAAACGCAAAUAACACAGUUUUUAAAUUCUCAAAGAAUCUGCAUAGACAUUUAUCCAAAGAAGAUGCACAAGCCUCCAAGAAGUACAUGAAAAGAUUCUCAACAUCAUUAGCCGUCAGGUAAAUACAAAUCAAAAUGGCAAUAAGGCACUACAUCAGUUGAAACAGGAUGACUAUACUAAGACAAACAGAUAAGAAGUGUUGGUGAAAAGAUGUUAAAAUUGGAACUCUCAUCCACUGCUGGUGUGAAUGUAAGUUGUUCCGGCCAUUUUGGGAAACAGUCUGGUAGUUCCUCAGAAGGUUAAAUCUAGAGUUACCACAUGACCAAAUAAUUCUACUGCUAGGUAUAUAGAACAAAGAAACAUGAAAACAUUAUGUCCACAUAAAAACUUGUACAUGAAUGUUUAUAUCAGAUUUUUUUUUUUUUUUUUUUUUGAGACAGAGUUUCACUCCUGUUGACCAGGCUAGCGUGCAAUGGCUCAAUCUCGGCUCACGGCACCCUCUGCCUCCCGGGUUCAAGCGAUUAUCCCACCUCAGCCUCCUGAGUAGCUGGGUUUACAGGUGCCUACCACCAUGCCUGGCUAGUUUUUUUUUUUUUUUUGUACUUUUAGUAGAAACGGGGUUUCACCACGUUGGCCAGGCUGGUCUUGAACUCCUGACCUCAAGUGAUCCACCCGCCUCAGCCUCCUAAACUGCUGGCAUUACACAGGCGUGAGCCACUGUGCCCAGCUGGAAAUCUUUAAAGGUAUUCAAUUCCAUGCAAUUGUGAAGCAGAUUCAGAUCUUAAAAAAAAAAAUUAAUGACACCUUAAUAUUAAAUAAUAUAGAAGCAAUAAUGUAAAUAAUGUAAAUUAAGGCUUUAAUAUGGCAUGUAUAACUAAAUGGAUUAAAUUCUGUUGAAAGACAAAUUCAUUAGGUGAAAAUAUUUAUGUAUUACAGGAAACAUAAAUUGAUACAAAAAUGUUAAAAGUAGGCCGGGUGUGGUGGCUCACAUCUGUAAUCCCAGCACUUUGGGAGGCCGAGGUGGGCACAUCACCUGAGGUUGGGAGUUUGAGACCAGCCUGACCAACACUGAGGAACCCCAUCUCUAUUAAAAAUACAAAAUUAGCCAGGCCUGGUGCCACACGCCUAUAAUCCCAGCUGUUCGUGAGGCUGAGGCAGGAGAAUCACUUGAACCUGGGAGGCAGAGGUUGCGAUGAGCUGAGAUCAUGCCAUUGCACCCCAGCCUGGGCAACAAGAGUGAAACUCCAUCUCAAAAAAAAAAAAAGUUAAAGGUAAAGGAUGGACAACAUUAUAUUCAGUGGGAUUUACAUCAUCAUAAAACAUUAAAAGUACAGAUUAGAUAAUUUUAUUAUUUCAAAAUGAAGUUAACAGUGAGGAUACAGCCAAGCAAUUAUGCAUCUGAGGGAAAAAUGAAAAUAGGUCCUUUCCUCUUUCUAUGUGCUAAAAUAAAUUCUAGAUGGAUUAAGGACUUAAAUUAUAAAUGACUUGAGAAAAUAUAAUUAAAACUUGAGAAAAUGUAAUUUCAUCUUUUGCAGCAUGUGUUACAGGACAGUAUUACCAUCUCAAAGAUCUGUGAGUUGUGGCUUAUGUGACAGCAAAUAAUUCAAAUUGGCUAAAGAGAGGAGUUCUGGUGUUGGUAGGGAUCCCCAAUUAGUUUGGGUGGCUUUUUAUUCUCAGCAAUGAAUUCAACUUCACUGAACGGGUUCUAUGAUAGGCAAACUAUAUAGUUAGAAAUAUUUAACUUACUUGCACCUUUUAUCAGCAGUUUUACUUGUCUCCCCUAAGCAUUCUCAUGCAGACAUUUUCCAGGUGAAAUACCUCUCCUCAGAGCCGGAAGUUUAACCAGUUAUGAAGUGUGUAAUGUUAAUGACCAUUUAGUUCAUGUUUUUCAUGAAGUUUAACAAAUUUACUCUGAGCUGGCACUCUGCAUUCUUACUAUAUAUUGUAAUAAUUGCACAGCCAUGGUAUAGCACCGUGUCCUUAAAUAACUUACAUCAGUGAAAGGCUUCUUUACCACCAGUAGGCUUCACUAUUUCACACAACAUGGAGUAGAGAAGGAUGUCACAAGGAAGAGAGAUCAAACUUUAACCAUAAAAGAAAAAAAAUUAUUUAACUUGACUAUAUUAAAAUUAGGAAGAGCCUAAUAAGAUACCUGUAACUCAUAUAACAAAGGAUUGACAAGGAAUAUGUUUUUGGUUUUUGGUUUUUUUUUGUUGUUGUUUUUUUUUAAGACAGUGUCCCACUCUGUUGUCCAGGCUGAAGUACAGUGGUGUGAUCUCGGCUCACUGCAACCUCCAUCUCCCGGGUUCAAGCGAUUCUCUUACCUUGUCCUCCCAAGUAGCCGGGAAUACAGACGUGUGCCACCACACCCAGCAAAUUUUUGUAGUUUUUAGUACAGACAGGGUUUCACCCUUUUGGCCAGGGUGGUCUCGAACUCCUGGCCUCAGGUGAUCCGUUCGCCUCAGCCUUCCAGAGUGCUGGGAUUACAGGCUUGAGCCACUGCACCUGGCCGGAAUAUGGUUUAUAAUAUGUUAAGUAUGCUUUGAAAAUGAAAGAGGAAAGACACCCCAAGAAGUCAUGAGCAGGAAAUAACCAGGAAUUUUUACAGACAAGUAAACAUAGCUAAUAAACAUAGGAAAAGAUGAUAGUAAUUAGGGAAACCCAAAUUAAGACAAUGAGAGCUAAUUCUUUAUCCAAGUAGAUUGGCUAAAAUCAAAUCUGGCAAUACCAAGGGUUCAAGAGGAUGUGGCUCAGUGGUAACUCUUACGUAUUGACUGUAUGGAUGCAAACUGGUAAAACUGCUCCAGGAAAUAAUUUGGUUUUCUUGAAAAGUUGAACAUGGAUACCUUUUCAGUAUCUAGAAAUUCACUCAGGAAAUGCUUACACAUAAGCCCCUUGAGACAGAAAUAAUCAGAAUAGCAUUGUUGUGUCAGAACAUCAACAAGAACUGGAAAUGUAAUCCCAGCACUUUGGGAGGCUAAGGCAUGAGGAUCACUUCAGCCCAGGAGUUUCAGACUAGCGUGGGCAACAUAGUAAGACCCAAUAUCCACAGAAUUUUUUUUACAAAUUAGCCAGUUGUGGUGGUGCAUGCCUGUAAUCCCAGCCUCUUAGGAGGCUGAGGUGGGAGGAUAGCUUGAGCCUGGGAGGCUGAAGCUGCCAUGAGCCAUGCUGCACUCCAGCCUGGGUAACAGAGCAGCAAGACCCUGUCUCAAAAAAAAAAAAAAAGGAACUGGAGGUGACCCAAAGAUCUUUCACAAAUGAUCAGAUAAACAAAUUUUGGUAUAUCUACCCAAAGAAUUAUUACAGUGCAAAGAAGAACACGAAUUAUUGCUAUACGUAAGCACAUGGAUGAAUUUUGUACAUAUACAUAACUGAAAAAACAAGUAUUAGCUAUAGUUUGCUCAACAACAAAAUUAAACAGUAUAUUUGUUUACAUAUGACAUUUAUGAUGAAACUGUAGAAAAAGUAAUAGAAUUAUAAACUAAGUUUAGGAUACAUCAUCAGGAUGGAGAAGAGGUGCAAGGGGCAUAGUUUGGAGAAACAUAAGUAAAUGCAGGUUACUGAUAGUAUUCUACUUAUUUGUUGCAGGUGUUUCAAAGAUGUUCACUUUAUUAUACUUUGUAAUUAACACAUAUUACAAGUCUUUUGUAUGCAUCAAAUGUAGAGGCAUUUUUUUACUCCAGAGCUUAAAUUUCAGCACGUUUUACUAAUUUGGGCCUUUUCCAAAGGCCCUUAGAAGGGCCAUAGUAACAAUAUGUUCACGUGGUUGGAUGUUUUCAUCAGAUUUACAAUAGUAAGAUAUUUUAAGUAUAGUCAUUUAAGACCCCUGUCUCUCUUCACCUUGAUUUCUUCUUUGUGUCAGCUGGCAGUAGAGUGGUUUCAGGCAUUUUGUGAUUGGGGGAUUUAUUUGUGUUUAGUGGGAUGUGUUUGUGAUUCAGAGUCAUUUCUGGAUGUAGGUAAUUAUAGCCUGUCAGCCUGAUUGUGUUGGGAAUGUGGUCUCUGGUGCCUGGCACCUGUAAUAUGUGAGUAUUAGAGAAGCCAAAGUGCAAAUUAUGGAACCAGAAGGUAAUCAGGAAAAAAUUCCCAAUUAUCUGAUGUUUAAAAUUUUAAGUGUAGGAUUUCGUUCUCAUCAAUUUCCAGUCAAAACAGCACUUUUCUCCUGUCAAAAAUAACAUAGCACAUUCAAUUAUAAAUUCACCAUAUAUUUAUUUUCUUUUUUUGAUAGGAAUCCUGCUUUUUUUUUUUCUUUGAGACACGGUCUCACUCUGUCACCCUUGCUGGAGUGCAGUGGUGCAAUCACAGAUCACGGCAGUGUCUAAUUCCUGGGCUCAAGUGAACCUUUUGCAUCAGCCUCCUGAAUAGCUGAGACCACAGGAUAUGAAAGAUGGCAAGUCCAGAUAGAAGUAAACGGAAGAUAUUAAAAGCCAAAAAGACAAUGCCCCUAAGUUGCCGGAAGCAAGUAGAGAUGCUGAAUAAGUCAAGGAAUGUUGAAGCGCUGAAAACAGCAAUUGGGAGUAAUGUUCCAAGCGGUAAUCAGAGUUUCAGUCCUAGUGUCAUAACUAGGACGACUGAAAUAACCAAAUGUAGCCCUUCUGAAAAUGGUGCAUCCUCAUUGGACUCUAAUAAAAAUUCAAUAUCAGAGAAAAGUAAAGUAUUCUCUCAGAAUUGCAUAAAACCAGUAGAAGAAAUUGUUCAUUCAGAAACAAAAUUGGAACAAGUUGUUUGUUCGUACCAAAAGCCAAGUAGAACAACAGAAUCCCCCAGCAGAGUCUUCACAGAAGAGGCAAAAGAUUCACUGAACACUUCUGAAAACGAUUCUGAGCAUCAGACAAAUGUAACAAGAUCCCUUUUUGAGCAUGAGGGGGCUUGUAGUCUAAAGUCCAGUUGCUGUCCACCCAGUGUAUUGAGUGGUGUUGUUCAGAUGCCAGAGUCUACAGUAACCAGUACCGUGGGUGACAAGAAAACUGACCAGAUGGUUUUCCAUUUAGAAACAAACUCCAAUUCAGAAUCACAUGAUAAAAGGCAAAGUGACAACAUUUUAUGUUCAGAAGACUCAGGUUUUGUGCCUGUUGAGAAAACACCUAAUUUGGUGAAUUCAGUCACUUCUAACAACUGUGCUGAUGACAUUUUGAAAACUGAUGAGUGUAGUAGAACCAGUAUUUCAAAUUGUGAAAGUGCAGACUCAACAUGGCAGUCAUCACUUGACACUAAUAACAACAGCCAUUAUCAAAAGAAGAGGAUGUUUUCAGAAAACGAGGAAAAUGUUAAACGCAUGAAAACUUCAGAGCAAAUUAAUGAAAAUAUUUGUGUAAGUUUGGAAAGGCAAACAGCAUUCCUGGAACAGGUCAGACAUUUGAUUCAGCAGGAGAUCUAUAGCAUAAAUUAUGAACUAUUUGAUAAGAAACUGAAAGAAUUGAACCAACGCAUUGGGAAGACAGAGUGCAGAAAUAAGCAUGAAGGAAUAGCUGAUAAACUUUUGGCAAAAAUAGCAAAACUUCAAAGACGUAUUAAAACAGUAUUAUUAUUUCAAAGGAAUUGUUUGAAACCAAACAUGUUAUCCAGUAAUGGAGCCUCUAAGGUUGCAAAUUCAGAGGCUAUGAUUUUGGAUAAGAAUCUUGAGUCAGUUAAUAGUCCAAUUGAAAAGUCUUCUGUGAAUUAUGAGCCUUCUAACCCUUCCGAAAAAGGAAGUAAAAAAAUUAAUUUGUCAUCAGAUCAAAAUAAGUCUGUUUCUGAAAGUAACAAUGAUGAUGUUAUGUUGAUUUCUGUGGAAAGUCCUAAUUUGACAACUCCAAUUACAUCAAAUCCAACAGAUACCAGAAAAAUUACAUCAGGAAAUUCUAGCAAUUCUCCCAAUGCUGAAGUUAUGGCUGUACAGAAGAAACUUGAUUCUAUAAUUGAUUUGACAAAAGAAGGCCUAUCCAACUGCAAUACAGAAAGUCCAGUAUCCCCCCUGGAGUCACAUUCGAAAGCUGCUUCAAACUCAAAGGAAACAACCCCAUUGGCACAAAAUGCAGUCCAGGUUCCUGAGUCCUUUGAGCACCUGCCACCUCUCCCAGAACCACCAGCACCACUACCUGAAUUAGUAGACAAAACCCGAGACACACUUCCUCCCCAGAAGCCUGAGCUCAAAGUGAAACGGGUUUUCAGACCCAAUGGCAUUGCCCUGACUUGGAAUAUAACCAAAAUCAAUCCCAAGUGUGCUCCUGUAGAAAGCUACCACCUCUUCCUGUGUCAUGAGAACUCUAAUAAUAAGUUGAUUUGGAAGAAGAUUGGAGAAAUUAAAGCUUUACCACUCCCCAUGGCCUGUACUUUAUCUCAGUUUUUAGCUUCCAACAGAUACUAUUUUACUGUCCAAUCAAAAGAUAUUUUUGGACGAUAUGGACCAUUCUGUGAUAUAAAAUCUAUCCCUGGGUUUUCUGAAAAUCUUACGUAAAAGGUGUUUAAUAAUGAUAUACUACUUUUUUUUUCAUAUUUGUUUGUUUGCAAUGUUACUGUAAUACUAUUUGCCAUUGUAAAAGGCCAGCUCAGAUUGUGAGCCCUUUCUAUUGGGACAGUCCUCUUCUAUAUGUUUUAAGUGGCCAGUAAUUUAAUGAAUUUCUGGUUUGUAUUAAAUAUGUCCUUCCAAUGGAUAAGUUCUAAAACAUACGCUAUCAUUGGCCCAUGUUGCUGAGGUGCAUUGUGAACAAUACCUUUAGUGACUGUGGAACUGCUGCUUCUAUCAGAAGACCUAGGAUACAAGCAGCCACUGUUUCCUCCGUUAACAAUCAGCUUUUAGUAACCUGCUGUGGUCAGCAUAGCUACAGGAAAAGUCAGCCCUUGACUGAGGGCCAGAUCAUCCCUGGAGUGCACCUCUACUAAGAUUUUAUGAAAAGAUGACAUGUUGGGCUGCAUGAUAAAAGUUAAUUAUAAAAAUUAAAAGAUUUUUUUUUUUGAGAUGGAAUAUUGCUCUGUUGCCCAGGCUGGAGUACAGUGGUCACUGCAACCUCCAUCUCCCUGGUUCAAGCAAUUCUCCUAUGUCAGCCUCCCAAGUAGCUGGGACUAUAGUCACUUGCCACCAUGCCCGGCUAAUUUAUUUUUAGUAGAGAUGAGGUUUCACCUUGUUGGUCAGGCUGGUCUCAAACUCCUGACCUCAGGGGAUCCACCCGCCUCGGCCUCCCGAAGUGCUGGGAUUAUAGGCGUAAGCCACCAUGCCUGGCCAAAAAUUAAAAGAUUUUAUGAAACGAAAUGGCUUCCCAUUCUUUCUAUUCAGCUUCUAAGUGGGCUAUUCAUUUGUGCUCUCCUCUUUUUUGUUUUGUUUUGCACUUUGUCAAUCAUUUGGGGAAAUAGCCUGGAGGUCUUUCCUGAAUCUGUUUGUAGACAUAAUAAAAUUUGUGUGCUGUGUACACAAAAACAUAAUGUAUCUUAUGAAAGCAUUACCCAACCUGUUUGAGUUGAGAAUGCAUUUGUCCACCUUUGAUUUGAGGCUUUAGUUUGCUGAUUUCCUAAAUGCUACCCUUUGAUCAUUUCCUGGCCACCAUCACAAUACUAAGGGGCUCAGAUGUGUCUUGUGCCCACCUCUUCCUGAGAAGAGAUGGAAGUGGAGCUGUGACUAGUACAAGCAGCCCAAGAAACUCUGAACGGGGCCCAAUGGAGGCAAACUUGAGCAAAUAAUUGGGAUGAUAAGAAACAAAAAUAAUCCCAACUGUUUGAAAGUUCGAAAGAGGGGCAUUCUUUUCUGGUACAUGGUGAGAGUUCAGGCUCCAGAGACUCAAAACGGAAUGGUUUUCCUUGGCAUUUUGUAAAUGCUCUCACAUCUGUAGCAAUAAAGCUGUUAUUUUCUGCA